ACAGUGAGCUGAGAUCGCACCACUGCACUCCAGCUUGGAGGACAGAGCGAGACUCCAUCUCAAAACAAACAACUGUGGAAAAGAGUGCGUCAUGGAGCUUAGAAAUCCCAGGAAAUCCAGGUGAAGAAAGUAGAGCUCUGGGCAGAGGAGAUGGCGUGGGCAGAGGAGAUGGCGUGUGCAAAGGCCCUGUGGUGUGUUCAGCCAGCACGUUCAGGGAGCAGAAGGGUGGCCAGUGUGGCCGAGGUGAGGUCAGAAGCGGGGUGAGGACACAGAGCUUGGGGGAGGCCUGGUGCCAGGAAGAGCUGCCAGGGGUCUUGAGCACAGGGGUGAUAACAUUCCCUGUGGGAAGUAAACUGUUGGGAAUUGCGGGGAGGGCAAGGAGGAGGCGCUGGACCAGAGGAGUGCUGGGGAGUAGGGAGUGUCAGAUUCCCAAGAUGCAUAGGAUAGAGGGGUCUAAAUGCACUUCAUUCAUUCAUUCAUAGCCCUGGGCCCUGGGCCCAAGUUGCCCAUCCACACUCCACCUCUGUCUGUCCUCUUCCAAGUCCCUGUGUAAAUAGAAACUGGCGCCUGCUGGGACAUGAGCCAAGAGUAUCAUGAACUCGGGGGGCUGAAACUCUCCCUGCUUUACAGAUGAGGAAACGGAGGCUCGGAGAGGCGAGGUGACCCCCGAGACCAUCCCACUGGGAGGUGGUGAAGCUGGUUUUGGAGGGCCCCCAUCUCCCAAUCCCGUUCUCUGGGUUGGAAGAGCCUGGGUCCCCAGACGCCUGGCUCCAGCUCGGUCCCUACACCUGUCUCCUCCCCUUUCCUACCUUUGUACUUCCAAUAAUUGGAAUAAUUAAGUCAAUAAUCCACUCCUCGGGAGCCUGAGCCUGGAGUGGGAGGCAGGAGAACCCUGGGUCACAUUCAACCUCUAAAUGCUGCGCAGCCUGGAAGAGUCGUUUUCUUCCCUGAAUCGCACUCGAUCCCCUGCACGAGGAGACAGGAGGACUUGCUGUGGAGGGGCCAGGAUGCCCCAGGAAUCAGCUAGUGCCAUGGAGGGGCCAGGAUGCCCCGGGAAUCAGCUGGUGCCGUGGAGGGGCCAGGAUGCCCCGGGAAUCAGCCGGUGCCAUAGAGGGCCAGGAUCCCCGGGAAUCAGCUGGUGCCGUGGAGGGGCCAGGAUGCCCCGGGAAUCAGCCGGUGCCAUAGAGGGCCAGGAUCCCCGGGAAUCAGCUGGUGCCGUGGAGGGGCCAGGAUGCCCCGGGAAUCAGCUGGUGCCAUAGAGGGCCAGGAUCCCCGGGAAUCAGCUGGUGCCGUGGAGGGACCAGGACGCCCCGGGAAUCGGCUGGUGCCGUGGAGGGGCCAGGACGCCCCGGGAAUCAGCUGGUGCCAUAGAGGGCCAGGAUGCCCCAGGUAUCAGCUGGUGGCAUAGAUGACCAGGAUGCCCCGGGUAUCAGCUGGUGGCAUAGAUGGCCAGGAUGUCCUGGGUAUCAGCUGGUGCCAUGGAAGGGCCAGGACACCCCGGGUAUCAGCUGGUGCCAUAGAUGGCCAGGAUGACCUGGGUAUCAGCUGGUGCCGUGGAGGGGCAGGAUGCCCCGGGAAUCAGCUAGUAUCAACUGAGCACCCCGCCUGCGGCAGGCCUGGAGGUCAGCCGGUUCCAUGUGCUCCCUGAGGAAUCGGGCUACUCCCCGGUGCCUCAGUGUCCCUCUCUGGAAACUGGCGAUGGUGGCCCUCCAGGGCCCUCCCACUGGGCUAACCCGUGAUGCACGAAUCAGUCAGGUCCCUCCUGGGAGCUCGCAGACAGUCCUGCUCCUGGGAUUGUUUUAUUGUUACGCCGUCCCCUCCCUUUCCUGAGGCUCCCAGGGUAAGUCUUCAAGCUGCACAGCUACCCAGUGGCCUCCUCAGCAUUGGAGCUCGGAUUGCAGCCCUCCCCUUUUUAAACCACCUCCCUGUAGGUCCUCCAAGCCUGUUAUCCUGGAGGCCACUGUGGGGCAGCCUUGGAUUCAGGCCUGGCUCUGGGAAGCCCCGGGUCCCUGGUGGGGCCCCCACCUGGGGGGAUGGAGGGCCAAAGCCUCCCAGCAUGAGGCGCCACGACUCAGGGCGGAGAGGGGCUGGUCGAUACCACCUGGGCCCCUCCUCCAGCUUGAGCCCGAAUCUGCAGCAUCCUGGUCUCCCAUCCUGGAGGGCUGCAGCGAGGCUGCUGCAGAGGGAAGCAGAAGGUUCUGUUGACCAGGAGAGGCUCCUGUUUACUUACCGAUGGUGCAGAGCUAAGCAGCCAGAAGGCCCCGGGCUCCCUGCCCCUGCCCCACCCAGGGUGGGGUCUGCGUCCGUCCACAGGGCAGGUGUUAGGACCCAUCCCAGGCCCUGCUGUCCUUGUCUGCAAUGGAGGAGGGUGGCUCUGUGGCCCCUGAGGCCCCCUCUCCUCGGGCCUGCUGAAAGAGCACUGUUUCGGGGCCAUCGUGGCGAUGCUAUUCACCCAUUUGUUUGGCAAAUGUUUACUGGAGACAUGGCUGGCCUGUGCCUUGGGGCCACUACAGGGACAGGACCUCCAGGACCCUCCUCCCGGCUCGGGCCCAGCAGAGACGGUGGACAGACCCCCAGGAUCCGGGCCCAGCAGAGACGGUGGACAGACCCCCAGGAUCCGGGCCCAGCAGGGGCGGUGGACAGACCCCCAGGAUCCGGGCCCAGCAGAGACGGUGGACAGACCCCCAGGAUCCGGGCCCAGCAGGGGCGGUGGACAGACCCCCAGGAUCCGGGCCCAGCAGGGGCGGUGGACAGACCCCCAGGAUCCGGGCCCAGCAGGGGCGGUGGACAGACCCCCAGGAUCCGUGCCCAGCAGGGGCGGUGGACAGACCCCCAGGAUCCGGGCCCAGCAGGGGCGGUGGACAGACCCCCAGGAUCCGGGCCCAGCAGGGGCGGUGGACAGACCCCCAGGAUCCGGGCCCAGCAGGGGCGGUGGACAGACCCCCAGGAUCCGGGCCCAGCAGGGGCGGUGGACAGACCCCCAGGAUCCGGGCCCAGCAGGGGCGGUGGACAGACCCCCAGGAUCCGGGCCCAGCAGUGACGGUGGACAGACCCCCAGGAUCCGUGCCCAGCAGGGGCGGUGGACAGAUCCCCAGGAUCCGGGCCCAGCAGGGGCAGUGGACAGACCCCCAGGACCCUCCUCCCGCCUCAGGCCCAGCAGGGGUGGUGGACAGCAGCCCAAGGGUAUUCUGCAUGGCAGCUGGAGCUGGGGUUCGGGGGCCCUGCUAGUCUGUGGUGGGGCCUGCCCAGGCUUCCUGGAGGCGGCGGCGGUGAAGGGGAGAAUUCCUCGGUGUCUGCCUCCUUGUCAGACUUCGGGGCUGCGUCGCGGUUGCCCCAGCACAAAAAUGAGGGCUCAUCAACGUUUGCUGGGUGAGCAAAGCUUAGAUGGGGUCACAGCUCCUCCGGGUUUCACUUUCCCCUCUGGACGGCAGGACUCUAACCCCUUAUUGCAAGGGUACGUGGAGAGUGGGGAGGCCUCAGCCCAGCUCUCUCGCCCUCCUGGACCCCUCUUCUACCACUGUGGCAGCAGCCGCUCCUCCCAGCUUGGGCCACAUCCAGACUUGGGGACAUUCCCAGAAUGCAGGAGGCUCCUGGACAAUCAAUAAUUCAAUAAAGCGCCAGGCGUCCGCCGGCUCCGGGUUGGUCCUGGGGAUAUGUUAUCUUGCUGGCUCCAAGCACGAGGAGGCUGGGAACUGCUCAGCUCGGUUCCAGAAGAGGAAACUGAGGCGGGGAGGGCAGGGAGGGAGGGAGAGAAGGAAGCAGUGAAGGCCGGGGCUGGCAGAUCACGAAGCAGCUGGCAGGAGGGGGGUCGGGGCCUCAGGAGGGGGGGACCCUGUGGUCUCAGGAACUGCCAGGAAGCCUGGGUUUGGACCUGGUCUUGCCCCCUAUGGGUUUCUCCAUCCGUGAAUCACACGCAUGUGCCUUCUCUCUUCGCCCCGACCCUCACGCUUUCCUGCUGUAUUCCUGUUCCGGGCGUCACCACCCCUGCAGUUCUAAGCUGCACCUGUACGCUCUGUGGGCAUCCUGCCCCUGCAUCACCAGGGCUGGGGCCACCUCCCUCCGUCCCAGCUGUGUCCCCGGUGGCCAGGUCACUGUCCAGCAUCAAGCGGGUGCUCAGGAAACGUUUGUCCAUGAAAUGAAGGAGCCCCCCCCUUCCAGGCUUCUUGUAGGGCUGCUGAGAGGUUGCCCAUUUAGUAAGACCUGCUGUCCUAGCUGUUCGGUCCUUGUUUCUGGAAGGAAACCCCCCACCUUCCUCAUCUACAGAUUGAGAAUUGCAGUAGGACCUGCGUACUGGGUUGUGUGAGAGUCAGAGACCCGCCAGGACGCUGGGAGGCUGGCAGGGAGGAAACGCUCCAUCAUAAACCCAGCUGCAUUUA